GGGCGGAGAGGGCAGGGAGCUGGGAUUUCGCGGGGCACAGUGAGGCCGGGCAUGUAGGCAGGUGGGACUUGGGCGUGCCCUGCUGUCUCCUGCUCUGUGUUUGUGUGAGGCAGCGCCUCCUCUGCCCUGCCAGGCUGGGGAUACCCGUUUCUCUAGCUUGGAGCCACCAAGAUAGAGGACAAACACUUCUGUGAUUCAGUCCCCAGACUGUCUCUGACUUAAUCCCUUGGGUUCAAGCCCUAUGUGGGAGAGCAAGGGCACACACUGCCUAAUCCGUGGUGUCCCCCCCAGGACAAUGGCGUCUCUUGGCCACAUCUUGGUUUUCUGUGUGGGUCUCCUCACCAUGGCCAAGGCAGAAAGUCCAAAGGAACACGACCCGUUCACUUACGACUACCAGUCCCUGCAGAUCGGAGGCCUCGUCAUCGCCGGGAUCCUCUUCAUCCUGGGCAUCCUCAUCGUGCUGAGCAGAAGAUGCCGGUGCAAGUUCAACCAGCAGCAGAGGACUGGGGAACCCGAUGAAGAGGAGGGAACUUUCCGCAGCUCCAUCCGCCGUCUGUCCACCCGCAGGCGGUAGAAACACCUGGAGCGAUGGAAUCCGGCCAGGACUCCCCUGGCACCUGACAUCUCCCACGCUCCACCUGCGCGCCCACCGCCCCCUCCGCCGCCCCUUCCCCAGCCCUGCCCCCGCAGACUCCCCCUGCCGCCAAGACUUCCAAUAAAACGUGCGUUCCUCUCGACAGCACUUUGUCGGUCUCGGUCCCUCAGCGCGAAACGCCAGCGCCACUGGGCCCCAGCA